CCUUUCCAGCCCCGGUACCGGACCCUGCAGCCGCAGAGGUGAGUUUCUGUGGCGUUCGAGUUCCAUCGGCUCCCAUCCGGGCUAUCCUGCCGCCUUAGCGGCUGCUUCUCCCCAGGAUGCGGGCAGGGGGCCUCUCUCCCACUCCCCACACACCGAUUUCUGAGUAGCGAUAGGGGCUGGAGGCUUAUUUUAUGGGGUAGGGGGCCGCUGGUAGGCGAAGAUUGUCCGAGGGAGAGGGGGAGGAUGAAGCCAGUGAGUGGCGGAGACUUGCCAGAUGUUGAUGCCUAAGAAGAACCGGAUUGCCAUUUAUGAACUCCUUUUUAAGGAGGGAGUCAUGGUGGCCAAGAAGGAUGUCCACAUGCCUAAGCACCCGGAGCUGGCAGACAAGAAUGUGCCCAACCUUCAUGUCAUGAAGGCCAUGCAGUCUCUCAAGUCCCGAGGCUACGUGAAGGAACAGUUUGCCUGGAGACAUUUCUACUGGUACCUUACCAAUGAGGGUAUCCAGUAUCUCCGUGAUUACCUUCAUCUGCCCCCGGAGAUUGUGCCUGCCACCCUACGCCGUAGCCGUCCAGAGACUGGCAGGCCUCGGCCUAAAGGUCUGGAGGGUGAGCGACCUGCGAGACUCACAAGAGGGGAAGCUGACAGAGAUACCUACAGACGGAGUGCUGUGCCACCUGGUGCCGACAAGAAAGCCGAGGCUGGGGCUGGGUCAGCAACCGAAUUCCAGUUUAGAGGCGGAUUUGGUCGUGGACGUGGUCAGCCACCUCAGUAAAAUUGGAGAGGAUUCUUUUGCAUUGAAUAAACUUACAGCCAAAAAACCUUAA